GCAGGUGGGCUAUGGUUGCUUGGAGAGUGCAUCCGGCCCGGUACUUGUGAUCGGAGGAGAGCCGGAUCGUCCUUCCUUGAACCCUCUGGGUAGGGCUGUGCUGAGGGGCUGGGCGGGGAGCACAGGCCGUGUCCGCUCGCUUGCACCUUUUCAGACUGCCGUGUCAGGCCUCGAGCCGGGCCCACCUGGAGCCCUCCCCUGCCCACCCGCCCCCAGCGCCCGAUAUCCGCCCCCGGCCCAGAAGGGCCGGGCUCGGUCAUCCCCAGUCCCGUCGCGGCCACUGACCCUUGAGAUCAGCCCUCCCCUCCCCACCUUCCCGUCCCAGGCCAGCCCAGGGCCCGAAGCCCACCCACUCGCGUCUCUAGCAGCCGCUCUUGUCCUCUGGGUACGGCUCGCGGGAGUGUUGGUUACCAUGGUGAAGCUGGCAGCCAAAUGCAUCCUGGCAGGAGACCCAGCAGUGGGCAAGACCGCCCUGGCACAGAUCUUCCGCAGUGAUGGAGCCCAUUUCCAGAAAAGCUACACCCUGACAACAGGAAUGGAUUUGGUGGUGAAGACAGUGCCAGUUCCUGACACGGGAGACAGUGUGGAACUCUUCAUUUUUGACUCUGCUGGCAAGGAGCUGUUUUCGGAAAUGCUGGAUAAAUUGUGGGAGAGUCCCAAUGUCUUAUGUCUCGUCUAUGAUGUGACCAAUGAAGAAUCCUUCAACAACUGCAGCAAGUGGCUGGAGAAGGCUCGGUCACAGGCUCCAGGCAUCUCUCUCCCAGGUGUUUUAGUUGGGAACAAGACAGACCUGGCCGGCAGACGAGCAGUGGACUCAGCUGAGGCCCGGGCAUGGGCGCUGGGCCAGGGCCUGGAAUGUUUUGAAACAUCCGUGAAAGAGAUGGAAAACUUCGAAGCCCCUUUCCACUGCCUUGCCAAGCAGUUCCACCAGCUGUACCGGGAGAAGGUGGAGGUUUUCCGGGCCCUGGCAUGACGAGCUGGAGCAGAUCGUGCUGCACAACCGGAGAAGACAGAAUUACCUCUGCUCUUUUAAUAUAUAAUGAUGGCUUUAAAUAAAAUUAGGAGAAAAUGUC